GGAGGAACGGGAGCGGGCGCGCGCAGGUGCCGGGGAGCGGAGUUCCUGGAGGGGGUCCCAGGCUCAAGGACCUCGGCGAGGCCAAGGGGAGUCCGUCCCGGUUCCCGAGGCGCUGCCGGAGCUGACCCGGAGGCCCGGGAGGGGAGGGAGCGAGACACCGCCCCCGCUGGCGCCGGGAAGCGUCGCUCCUUCUCGCUGACCUUGGUCUCGCUUGUCGCCUCGCCCUUGGCCACACGCACCGACGACGCGGGGCCCGGGAGAUGGACAGACGGGCCUCUGGAGGGACGGAGACCUAGAACAUAGGCACACACACUGCCCCGGUAGCCCCGCGGGCUCCGGGGCGUCCGGUCCUCACCCACCCCGUGGCCGGGCCCCUCCAGCCCAGGGUUAAUGCCAACGAGUUUCCACCUCCAGCGGCUCCUAGAGAGGCCGCGGCGCGAGCCGGCGGGGGGACCUGGCCGCGGACGGACACUUCCUGUGCGGGGGAGGGUGGGGGGGUGCUGGGCGGCCGUUGGACAGUGCAGCCCAGCCCGGGGCCGGGGUCCAGAAGGCAACAUGAGUGAGAAUGAGGAAGAGGAAAUUUCUCAGCAAGAAGGCAGUGGGGACUAUGAAGUCGAAGAGAUACCAUUUGGGCUUGAACCCCAGAGCCCUGGGUUUGAGCCACAAAGCCCAGAGUUUGAACCCCAAAGCCCCAGAUUUGAGCCUGAAAGCCCGGGGUUUGAGUCCCGAAGCCCUGGGCUUGUGCCCCCAAGCCCUGAGUUUGCACCCAGAAGCCCUGAAUCAGAUUCUCAGAGCCCUGAGUUUGAAUCCCAGAGCCCUAGGUAUGAACCCCAAAGCCCUGGCUAUGAACCUCGGAGCCCCGGGUAUGAACCCCGGAGCCCUGGCUAUGAAUCUGAGAGCUCUAGAUAUGAAUCCCAGAACACUGAGCUCAAAACCCAAAGCCCAGAAUUUGAAGCUCAAAGUUCCAAAUUCCAGGAAGGUGCGGAGAUGCUUCUGAACCCCGAGGAAAAGAGUCCUUUGAAUAUCUCCGUAGGAGUUCACCCCCUGGACUCCUUCACUCAGGGGUUUGGGGAGCAGCCCACAGGGGACCUGCCCAUAGGGCCACCUUUUGAGAUGCCCACAGGGGCCCUGCUGUCUACACCGCAGUUUGAGAUGCUUCAGAAUCCCCUGGGUCUCACAGGAGCCCUUCGAGGUCCAGGUCGGCGGGGUGGCCGGGCCAGGGGUGGGCAGGGCCCUCGGCCUAACAUCUGUGGCAUCUGCGGGAAGAGCUUCGGGCGGGGCUCCACCCUGAUCCAGCACCAGCGCAUCCACACCGGUGAGAAGCCCUACAAAUGUGAGGUCUGCAGCAAGGCCUUCUCCCAGAGCUCUGACCUCAUCAAACACCAGCGCACCCACACUGGCGAGCGGCCCUACAAAUGUCCCCGUUGCGGCAAGGCCUUCGCCGACAGCUCUUACCUGCUUCGCCACCAGCGCACUCACUCUGGCCAGAAGCCCUACAAGUGCCCACAUUGUGGCAAGGCCUUCGGCGACAGCUCCUACCUCCUGCGACACCAGCGCACCCACAGCCACGAGCGGCCCUACAGCUGCACCGAGUGCGGCAAGUGCUAUAGCCAGAACUCGUCCCUGCGCAGCCAUCAGAGGGUGCACACCGGUCAGAGGCCCUUCAGCUGUGGCAUCUGCGGCAAGAGCUUCUCCCAGCGGUCGGCCCUUAUCCCCCAUGCCCGCAGCCACGCCCGGGAGAAGCCCUUCAAGUGCCCUGAGUGCGGCAAGCGCUUUGGCCAGAGCUCGGUGCUGGCCAUCCACGCCCGCACCCACCUGCCAGGCCGCACCUACAGCUGCCCCGACUGCGGCAAGACCUUCAAUCGCUCCUCCACUCUCAUCCAGCACCAGCGCUCCCACACGGGCGAGCGGCCCUACAGGUGCGCCGUGUGCGGCAAGGGCUUCUGCCGCUCCUCCACGCUUCUGCAGCAUCACCGGGUCCACAGUGGCGAGCGGCCUUACAAGUGCGAUGACUGCGGAAAGGCCUUCUCCCAGAGCUCCGACCUCAUCCGCCACCAGCGGACCCACGCGGCGGGCCGGCGCUGACCUGGGGCCCCAGCAGGGGUGGGAGGUGUGGGCAGAAGAUAAGGGGCCAGGGAGCUAGAGGAACCUUUAGGGAGGAUAGUGGAGAAGCCGCAGGAGAAUGGAGGAGCUGAGGAUGCUGGAAGAAGAGAACCAGGGUGGAGGAAGUGACAUGCCCUGGAGACUUGUGGGAAGUGGGUUGGAGGGAGGCCAGGCCGGCAGCGGGAGGCCCUGGGAGAAAUGGAGAGAGGUCAGCGGAGGGCUGGCCUCAGCCGCGGCUCCUUGGUGGGUGCCUGGCUUGGCAACUGCUAGAGCAGGGAGGGGGGAGGGCAGGGGAUUACCUAAUUAGAGUGGGUUAGCUUAGAUUGGUAGCUGCUGAAACUCUCGUUGAGUCAGGAGCGGGUAAAAGGUAGGUGGGGUGGGGAGUGGGGCCCCGGGGUGGGGCCUGGGCCUCUGCGUGCAAACCCCAGCCUCCCUCUUCUUCCUCAGGCUUUGGAGCCCCUGAGUUUGAGUUCAAUAAAAACUUUAUGUGGUAAA